CUGCGGUUUGCUGGGGGUCCACUCCAGACCCUUAUUGCCUGGGUCCCUCCUGCACCUGGAGGUAUCACCAGUGAAGGCUGCAAAACAGCAAAGAUGGCAUCCAGCUCCUUCCUCUGGAGACUCCAUCCCAGAGGGGCACCAACCUGAUGCCAGCUGGAACGCUCCUGGAGGAGGCAUUUGUAGACCCCUGUUGGGAGGUCUCACCCAGUCAAGAGGAAUGGGAUCAGGGACCCGCUUAAAGAAGCAGUCUGGCUGCCCCCUGGUGGAGCAGAUACGCUGUGCUGGGGGAAACCUCCCUCAUCCAGACCACCCAGACUCUCCAGAGCAUCCAGGUCCCACUGAAAGUAGCAGUCUGGCCAUGAUCUGCCACAGCAGCUGUGCUGCGCUGUGGGGAAUUCCUCCCAGUUUGGACCACCCUGACUCCCAGGAGCUGGCAGGCCAGGAUGGCCUACUUGAGCUGCAGAGAUAGUGUCUGUCCCUCCUACACGUCCACCCAGCUCGGUCGUCUCAGGCCGUCUCCAACGUCUACCACUGGCUGGCUGGAAUUACAAGACAUGCACCAGGUGGCGGAGCGGGUGGAGGCCCUGGGGCAGUUUGUCAUGAAGACCAGAAGGACCCUCAAAGGCCACGGGAACAAAGUCCUGUGCAUGGACUGGUGCAAAGAUAAGAGGAGGAUCGUGAGCUCGUCACAGGAUGGGAAGGUGAUCGUGUGGGAUUCCUUCACCACAAACAAGGAGCACGCGGUCACCAUGCCCUGCACGUGGGUGAUGGCAUGUGCUUAUGCCCCAUCGGGAUGUGCCAUUGCUUGUGGUGGUUUGGAUAAUAAGUGUUCUGUGUACCCCUUGACGUUUGACAAAAAUGAAAACAUGGCUGCCAAAAAGAAGUCUGUUGCUAUGCACACCAACUACCUGUCGGCCUGCAGCUUCACCAACUCUGACAUGCAGAUCCUGACAGCGAGCGGCGAUGGCACAUGUGCCCUGUGGGACGUGGAGAGCGGGCAGCUGCUGCAGAGCUUCCACGGACAUGGGGCUGACGUCCUCUGCUUGGACCUGGCCCCCUCAGAAACUGGAAACACCUUCGUGUCUGGGGGAUGUGACAAGAAAGCCAUGGUGUGGGACAUGCGCUCCGGCCAGUGCGUGCAGGCCUUUGAAACACAUGAAUCUGACAUCAACAGUGUCCGGUACUACCCCAGUGGAGAUGCCUUUGCUUCAGGGUCAGAUGACGCUACGUGUCGCCUCUAUGACCUGCGGGCAGAUAGGGAGGUUGCCAUCUAUUCCAAAGAAAGCAUCAUAUUUGGAGCAUCCAGCGUGGACUUCUCCCUCAGUGGUCGCCUGCUGUUUGCUGGAUACAAUGAUUACACUAUCAACGUCUGGGAUGUUCUCAAAGGGUCCCGGGUCUCCAUCCUGUUUGGACAUGAAAACCGCGUUAGCACUCUACGAGUUUCCCCCGAUGGGACUGCUUUCUGCUCUGGAUCAUGGGAUCAUACCCUCAGAGUCUGGGCCUAAUCAUCUUCUGACAGUGCACUCAUGUAUACCUGAGAAUUUGAAAUCUUCACAUGUAAAUAGAUAUUACUUCUAGAGGAGCUUAGAGUUUAUUGCAGUGUAGCUUAGGGGAGCAACCCAUGGCUCACAGGUCACUAAGCGUCUCCAAUAUGACUAUUAAAACUGUCACCUCUGGAAAUACACUAGUGUGAGCCUUCAGCACUGCGAGAAUACCUUCAAGUACAGUAUUUUUCUUUUGGAACACUUUUUAAAAUGUAUCUGUUUUUAAGGUUAUUCUAAAUUAUAGUAGCCUCAACUCAUUCUGUCACCAGUAGAAUUCAGCAGUUAAUAUAUUCCAUAUUAUUUCUUUGAAUCAAUUCAUUUUCAGAGCACUUUAAAGUCUGAUAUUUCUCGAUGUGCACUGUGAUGCCUGGAACCUUCCUCUGGAAGUGCUGAUUUUAUGGACUGAGGACUGGUGACUGGUCUGUGAUAGAAGCAAAUUCCAAUUCCAAAUGUAAUUAGACAAAAAUCAUUUUUUUAGAAUGUGUUUUUAUUGUAAAAGUAUCUUUUUCAGCUUCCUGUUCUAUUGUCUUUUUUCAGAUACAACAUUUUUGUCUAUGGUGAACUGCUGUAAAUGACGCAGAGAAAUGCCUAAAAAGGACAGGUGGUUUGACUCAUGGAUGAUGAUGAUGUCACUGUGCCACUUGGACAGGGCGUUUUCUCUGAAUUGAAGGGAAAGCCAAUGGUGUUUGUAAACAAAUGCUUCUGAGAGCAAAGAAAAGUCUUCUGUGUGGGAACACAAGAUAGUAAACUUAUUUAAAAACCUAUUAGUAGAAUUAGUGGAAACACUUAGGUUAAAGUGAAUCUUGUCCAUAUAAAUUAUAUUCAUGGCCGGGCGCGGUGGCUCACGCUUGUAAUCCCAGCACUUUGGGAGGCCGAGGCGGGCGGAUCACGAGGUCAGGAGUUCGAGACCACGGUGAAACCCUGUCUCUACUAAAAAAUACAAAAAAUUAGCCGGGCGUGGUGGCGGGCGCCUGUAGUCCCAGCUACUCGGAGAGGCUGAGGCAGGAGAAUGGCGUGAACCCGGGAGGUGGAGCUUGCAGUGAGCCGAGGUCGAGCCACUGCAGCCUGGGUGACAAAGCGAGACUCCGUCUCAAAAAAAAAAAAAAAUUAUAUUCAUAUGUAUUGCAUUGCAAUUAUAAUUACAUAUGCAGAUUGAUUGAUAGUCAUGAAUAAUAACGUCUGCUCCUCUUACAUAGAAAAACGAUAUUAAAAGAAGAUCUUCUCUUUAUUUGAGACUCAGAAUUCCUUCUAGAAGAAGGAAGUGCUUUUUGUUAUAGGAUCCCUUCUUUUCCUUUUUUUGUUUUUUUGUAAGAUGUAGAUGCUUAUUCUUUGCUUUAGAAAACUUCUCACUUAAAAAGAUGGCAUGCACCUAGGGGAAUAAAAGGUCACCUCAGACACCAGGUGUCAUUCCUGGUGAGGCCUGCCUCGUCGGUGGCCUGGGGUCUGCCGGCAGGUUCUGGCUGCACCUGAAGGCUGCGUGCACCUUGUCCCCUGGACAGGUCUCCUUUCCUGGCCCUGCUCCAGCCCAGCCCUUCUUCUAGUGGUAGCUCUGGCUUUGCAGGCCCAGCUCCAGGCCCUGCUCCUCAGAGAGACUCUUCCAGAGCUGGAGCUGGGCACAGCCAUAAGACAGGACUGGACCAGAUGCUCCUGUAAACAUCCAGGGGUGUGCCAGGCCCACCCUCACAACUGCUUGUUCAGGUAUCGUGAUGGGCCACUCGGUCCAAAAUCAGCCAGGCCAUCUUUUCCAUCAUCUCACUUCAAAUAAACAUAAUAAUUAUAUUUGAUCAUUUGCAGAGCAGUUACUGGUGGUUUUAUUGUACACUGGGGUCUGGGGUAGAGAGAGAAAAAUGAAGGGCCUCUGCCUUCCUCCAGGGAGCCCAGAGAGAGUGCUUUUUAGUCCCAGUAGAUUCCAGUCUGGGCAGGGGCUCAGGAAAUGGGCCCAGUGUCUGGCCAGCUCCUGCCAGGUGCUGAAGGGGUCAGGGCACCAUGGGAUUCCUGAGCUCUGCUCCAGAAUGUCCCACAGUGGCCCCUGGUGCAGCUGGCCUCCUUGUGGUGGCAUCCCCAACCCUCUCUCCCACAGCCAUUUUUUUUUUUGUCUCUGCACUGUGCCUUCCGGCUCCCAGAAGUGCAGGAAGGCACGAGAAAGGAAGGAAAGGUGGCCCAGGGAAGCACAUUCCAGGUUCCAUGUUUGGAGAGGUGGAGAGCAUCUUCAGGAUAUGUGCAAAGUAGACUGUGACUUUCCAAUCCAAAAAGCCACUUUAAGGGCCCAGGGAAAGUAUUCCAGAGAAUGCUUCCACUCCCCGCAUGGGCAGGAAGCCUCCUUCGCUGUGAGCAUGCGCUCUCGCAGUGGGUGCUGUCGGGAUUUGCUGAUGAGAUACUUGAUUUGGACUAUGUGACAGCAUGUGGAGACUCAGGGGUAAGCUCCAUGGGAUAGAUUGUAUUUUGCAGAUUGAAAAUAAUGCUGAGUGCAUUUUAUAAUCAGCUUUUCUUUUUUCCAGAGGACUUGGGGAUAAACCUACCAAACCAAUUGUGGUGAAGGGGCCAAACAGAUGGGCCCCCAGGGGUGUAGAGCCUUGGGCAGCCCCCUCCUGGGCCAGAAAAAAGAAAGUUCAGGCAGAAAGGUGUGGGUGAUGGGUAUUUAUGGGAAAUAUCUGUGACAUGAAGCCAAGUCCAGUGCUUUAGAAUGCGCGGUCAGCCUCUCACCGGUGGGGCCCUGGCAGCCGUCCCUCUUCUCCCAGGCGAGCCAGAGGUGGGCAUCCCGUUGCCACUGCCCUCUUCCCGCUCUUCUACCUCCUUUGCACCCUUCUCUAGGUUAUAAGUGGCUUAAAACAGCACAGGGUUGUAAGGGCCUUUGUGUCCCGGGCUCUCAUAGUUGCCAGGCCAGCUGGCUGAAAGGUGGCACCACCGAUACUGGGACUCCUCUGUGAGUUAGAGGGAUGCCUUGGUGACAUAAGAGGGCUGGCCUUCAUUCACACCCACCUCUGUCACGGUCACAGAAUAUAUGAUAAUAUCUGAGUUUUUCUCAGCCUCAGUUUCCCCAUUUGUAACAUGGGAUGGGACUAAAAUAUGUAAAGUGCCUACCUCAGCCUUUAGCACAUCUUCAGGAAGGGUUAGUUCCCAGCUUCUCCCUGUGUCCUCCUCAGUCCCCUUCCUAUUUGCCCCCCUCCCUUCUCCCUCCACCUAUCUUCCCUCUUUCUCUUCCCUUCCCCUCCUCCUCCCUCUCUCCUCCCUCUCUCCCAUUUCCCCCUCCCUCCCUCCCAUCUCCUCCUCCCUCCCUCCCAUCUCCUCCUCCUCCCUCCCAUCUCCUCCCUCCCAUCUCCUCCUCCCUCCCAUCUCCUCCUCCCUCCCAUCUCCUCCUCCCUCCCAUCUCCUCCUCCCUUCCUCCUGUCACCCCUCCUCCCUCCCUCUCAUCACCUCCUCCCUCCCUCCCAUCGCCUCCUCUCUCCUUCCUAUCUCCUCUUUCCUCUUCUCUGCCCCCUCCCCCUCUCCUCAUUCAUCCGGACUCCUUUUUCUAACCCUUCUCAAUCUUCCCCCAUUCCUCAUCUCCUCUUCCUCUGUCUCCCUGUUCCACCUCUCUCCUGGUCUCCUUCCUUCCCCUUCUGCUGUUUCUCCCUCCCUCCUCCUCCCUUCCCAUUCCCCUUCCCCCAGCACUUCCUUUUCUCCCCAUCUCCUCCCCAUUCCCCUUCCCCCAGCUCUUUCUUUUCUCCCCAUCUCCUCCCCAUCCAUAGGCAGCCCCCACUCAUAUAGCAAAUUAGUAAUUCUCAUCAGUUAGAGCUUCGUCUGGGCUAGUGGUUCUCAAACUUUUUGGUCUUAGGAUCUCUGUACACUUUUUUUUUUUUUUUUUUUUUACGUGGAGUUUUGCUCUUGUUGCCCAGGCUGGAGUGCAGUGGCGCGAUCUCGGGCUCACUUCAACCUCCGCCUCCUGGGUUCAAGCGAUUCUCCUGCCUCAGCCUCCCGAGUAGCUGGGAUUACAAGGCAUGCACCACCACGCCCGGCUAAUUUUGUAUUUUUAGUAGAGACCAGGUUUCUCCAUGUUGGUCACACUGGUCUCGAACUCCCAACCUCAGGUGAUCCUCCCACCUUGGCCUCCCAAAGUGCUGGGAUUACAGGUGUAAGCCACCGUGCCCAGCCUACACCCUUAAAAGUUAUUGAGGACCCCAAAUAACUUGCUCAUUGUGGAUUGUAUCUAUCCAUAUUUAUUGUAUUAGAAAUUAAGACUGAGAAAAAGUUAUAAAACACAAGAAUACAGAUGCACACGUUCCAUUAGCCAUCAAGGUGAUCUUUCUCCCAUGCCAGUAGUCUCUGGAAAAUUCCUGAGAGGAUGAAAAUAAAAAAAUCACCCAUACAAAAAAAAAAAGUGUCAAUAUUAUUAUGAAAAUAGUUUUGACCGUGAGGACCCCCUGAAAGGGUCUCAGGGACCCUCGGGGGCCCUGGAUCUUGCUUUGAGAACAGCUGAUCUGGGCUAAUGAGCCCUUUUCCAGCCCCUCUGUGUGAGACCUCCCAGAAACCACUAAGGGCCUUGGAAGAGCUUGGCAAAGAAAGAGGUGACAGGAUGAUUGAGGAGAGCCACCCUAGGGAAAGCCUUCAGAGGAGGCUUUGGGACAGCCCCGGUCGGUGGAGGAAGUCCCAGAGAGGCAGUCGGAAGGGCUAGGGACCAGCUGAGGCCUGUGACCUGAAAAUCCUUUCAAAAGAGGACGCCUGGAAGCCUGGGGAAGGCACAGUGGGUGGGGUAGAAGACUGGGGCUGAGGCCCAGGCCAUUCCCAAGCCUGGAAGAGCUGAUUGAGUGGGGAUUUGUAGAUCUUCAUUUCCCAAACUUGCCUGCUGAGAAGAAUCGUCCCACCCAUGGCAGGUUCCUGCACUGCGCCUUCAGGGCCCUGCCCUGAGAUCUGGACUGGGCGGGCCUGAGGUGGGCCAGGAAAUCUGAGCCGGAGGCCCACUGGGGAGGCCGCGAGUGAAUCUUGUCUCUGUGGAUCCUUUGUAAGGAUUGCCAUGCUAAACCACUUGCCCUCUCAUCCGUGACCGGAGAGAAUUGGGUCACUCUUCCAGACAUACCACAGACUCCUGCUUCUAGACAGCACUUGGCUGGAGCCAGGCUGGCCUUCAGGGUUGGUCAGUCUCCACAGGGGACUCUGGCCUCCCGUGGGCUGCCACAGGGCCAACCCCAGUGAAAGAAAUGAAAUGACUGAAUAUGUUCAUGUCAUUAGAAAAAGGAUGCAGCAGGGGGUGGGGAGGAGUUGGUUAAUGGAAUCAAAUUUGCAGCAAGAUAGGAGUCUAGUGUUUGGCGGCACUGUAGGGUGACUAUCGCUAACAAUAAUUUACUGUGUAUUUUCAAGUAGCUAGAAGAGAGAAUUUUGAAUGUUCCUGUCAACCUAAAUAACAAAGACAGGCUCGCUAAAGAUAUUUAAUCAAAAGUAGGGCAUUGCAACAGGAAUAUGUGUGCUGUAGUAAACUGUGUGCAUAUUCCAGGAGGUAAAGAAAAACAAAGGUGACUGGGCGCGGUGGCUCACGCCUGUAAUCCCAGCACUUUGGGAGGCCGAGGCGGGUGGAUCACGAGGUCAGGAGAUCGAGACCAUCCUGGCUAACACGGUGAAACCCUGUCUGUACUAAAAAAAAAUAUAUAUAUAUAUUAGCUGGGCGUGGUGGCAGGUGCCUGUAGUCCCAGCUGCUCGGGAGGCUGGGGCAGGAGAAUGGCAUGAACCCAGGAGGUAGAGCUUGCAGUGAGCCGAGAUGGCACCACUGCACUCCAGCCUGGGCGACAGAGCGAGACUCUGACUCAAAAAAACAAAGAAAAAAAAAAAGAAAAACAAAGGUUUUUAAAGGAAAAAAUGAGGAGGAUUACAUAAUGGUUUUGAAAUAAUUAUCCUUGGCUACAAAUAUCAAUAACAAAGGUCACACCAGUCCGAGGUUGGACAGGCAGUUGCUAGGCAGAUGUCUUUGCAGAAGUAAUUUUUGUGUGAGGUUGCAGCAGCCUAUGUGCAAGGUUGUAAUUUUUGCAGAAUCUUUUGUGAUCAUUUUUGGUAUUAGGCAUACAAGCAUGAGAAUCCCCUCUUCAUGGCCUCCCCAGCUCUAUUUGUCAUGGUUUGUUUUUUUAAAACACUAGUGACUCUAUUUGAAUUCUAACAACUUUCACAUUCCCAACACAAAUGAUAGACAUUUAAGGGAUUAAUAUGCUAAUUACCCUGAUCAUUACACAUUGUAUACAUGUAUCAAAAUAACACACUGUACCCCAUAAAUACAUACAAUUAUGUGUCAAUUAAAGAUCAUUAUUUUUAAAAAUAGGACCAGAAAAAAAGAUGCAGACCCUCUAGUAAGGAGAUGGGAUCAGGAGUGAUUCCAUGGUUAAUUUAACCCACAUAAACAACUAAUCGUAAGUAUGGUAUGAGCGUUUAUGUAAAGACUGUGACAACAGGAAAUGUCUGUCUUUGAACCCAAGGUUAUCUAACCAGCACACCAAUGGUGAAAGAUUAACUUUGUCAGAAACCAGGAACCAUGAAGCAGAGGUCACUGUUUCCAACCUGUGUGUUUUCCACGGUAAUUGGCAGCCUCCCCAAGGGAAAUUAAAACAUAUGUCCACACAGAAAUUUGAAUGCAAAUGUUCAUAGCAGCAUUACUCAUAAUAGCCCAAAGCUGAAACAGCCCCAAUGUUCCACAGUGGAUGAAUCGAUGAACAAAAUAUGGCGCAUCCACAGAAUGGAAUACAAAGAAAGAAAGCGUGGACACAUGCUGCAACAUGGAUGAACCUUGAAAAUAUUGUGCCAGGGGAAAGAAACCAGAGACAAAGAGCCACAUGUUGUAGGAUUCCAUGUAUAUGAAAGGUCCUAAUAAGCAAACUCAUAAAGACAAAAAGCAGAUUGGUGGUCACUUAGGGCUAGGGUGAGGAGUGACGGUUAGUGGGCACUGAGUUUCUCCGGGGGGAACUGAAUUAGAUGGUGGUGAUUGCACAAUUCUGUGAAUAGACUAAAAACCACUGGACUGUAAGAGGGUGAAUUUUUUGGUAUAUGAAUUACAUCUCAAUAAAGCUGUUACUUAAAACGUGGAAAAAAUAAUAAGCAGUCACUAGCUAUUCUCAAUAAAACAGAAACCACAUAGGUAAGACCAAUAUUGUCACAUUUUGGUUUUGGCUGAUAAUGGGGCAAGUGAGCAUAGUCACCGUUGCCAGAGGAUUUACCAUUUACAAAUAAAAGUUUCUGUGGAGUGACAACCUUUUACUGUGUGCCAGGUACUGUGCUAAGCACUUUGUAUAUACCGAUUCAUGUAAUCCUUGUGACAGCCCCGUGAUGCCCCAUUUUUAGAUGGGGAGAUUGAGGUUAGGAGAGUUGAAUAACUUGCCCAUAGCUGCACAGCUUCCAAGUUGCAGAGACAGGAUUUUCACCGAGUCUUAUUACAAACUGCCUCAUAUUGUGUGGACUGGAAAUUCUAUGUUGAGGUUAAUUUAUUCAUUUGUUGUUUAGUUCUUUUCAUCAUUGUUGAGUUACCAAUGGCAGUUCCAGAGGAUUUAUCAUUUACCCCAAAGCUACUGCAAAUCUAAGAGAAAACAAUGUUCUUGCUGCUAAAGUUUAAUGUACAAAAAGGUAAAAUCAUGACUGUCUUGCAAAUAAAACAUGAACAUGUAUCCAA